ACUUCCGGUGUCGCGCGGCGGCUCCCGGCAGGAGGCAGAGGGCACACCGCCAGCCCCAGGCCAGGCUGCGAGGGCCGCGGACCCGAGCCGGGAAGGACCUUGGGCGGACGAGCCGCGCGUCCCGCAGCCAUGGAGCAGGACGACCCGGUCGAGGCGCUGACGGAGCUGCGCGAGCGGCGGCUGGGCGCGCUGGAGCUGCUGCAGGCGGCGGCCGGCUCGGGCUUGGCAGCCUACGCGGUGUGGGCGCUGCUGCUCCAGCCCGGCUUCCGGCGCGUGCCGCUGCGGCUGCAGGUGCCCUACGUCGGCGCGAGCGCGCGGCAGGUGGAGCACGUGUUGUCGCUGCUGCGAGGACGCCCCGGAAAAACGGUGGAUCUGGGCUCUGGCGACGGCAGGAUCGUGCUGGCGGCCCACAGGUGCGGCCUCCGCCCGGCCGUGGGCUACGAGCUGAACCCCUGGCUGGUGGCGCUGGCGCGGCUGCACGCCUGGAGGGCCGGCUGUGCCGGCAGCGUCUGCUAUCGCCGCAAGGAUCUCUGGAAGGUGAGCCUGAGGGACUGCCGCAACGUGUCUGUGUUCCUGGCCCCUAGCGUGCUCCCGCUGCUGGAGGACAAGCUGCGGACAGAGCUGCCUGCUGGGGCCCGCGUGGUGUCUGGGCGCUUCCCACUCCCCACCUGGCAGCCUGUGACCGCGGUUGGCGAGGGCCUGGACCGAGUAUGGGCUUAUGAUGUUCCUGAGGGUGGGCAGGCUGGGGAGGCCGCCUCCUCGCGGAUACCCAUCCAGGCUGCCCCCGGACCUAGUUCUGCCCCCAUCCCGGGGGGCCUUAUUUCUCAGGCCAGCUGAGUAUUAGACACGAUAAAGACUCUGUGGGUUCUA